GUGGUCGUUGCUCCCUGACUGGCCGCGGCGGCCUCCAGGAAGCGGAAAAGCAAGGGGCGGUCGAGCUGGGCCGCCGCGCCCCACUGCUCGCCGCGCUGCUCUUUGACCUCGCAGGGUGUGAAGAAGAUGCGCAGCUCCACGCUGCAGGACCCGCGCCGCCGGGACCCCCAGGACGACGUGUACGUGGACAUCACCGAUCGCCUUCGUUUUGCCAUUCUCUACAGCAGACCAAAGAGUGCAUCAAAUGUACAUUAUUUCAGCAUAGAUAAUGAACUCGAAUAUGAGAACUUCUCCGAAGACUUUGGACCACUCAAUCUGGCAAUGGUUUACAGAUAUUGUUGCAAGAUAAAUAAGAAAUUAAAGUCCAUUACAAUGUUAAGGAAGAAAAUUGUUCAUUUUACUGGCUCUGAUCAGAGAAAACAAGCAAAUGCUGCCUUCCUUGUUGGAUGCUACAUGGUUAUAUACUUGGGGAGAACCCCAGAAGCAGCAUAUAGAAUAUUAAUCUUUGGAGAUACACCCUAUAUUCCUUUCAGAGAUGCUGCCUAUGGAAGCUGCAAUUUCUACAUUACACUUCUUGACUGUUUUCAUGCAGUAAAGAAGGCAAUGCAGUAUGGCUUCCUUAAUUUCAACUCAUUUAACCUUGAUGAAUAUGAACACUAUGAAAAAGCAGAAAACGGAGAUUUAAAUUGGAUAAUACCAGACCGAUUUAUUGCCUUCUGUGGACCUCAUUCAAGAGCCAGACUUGAAAGUGGUUACCACCAACAUUCUCCCGAGACUUAUAUUCAAUAUUUUAAGAAUCACAAUGUUACUACCAUUAUUCGUCUGAAUAAAAGGAUGUAUGAUGCCAAACGCUUUACGGAUGCUGGCUUCGAUCACCAUGAUCUUUUCUUUGCGGAUGGCAGCACCCCUACUGAUGCCAUUGUCAAAAGAUUUCUGGAUAUCUGUGAAAAUGCUGAGGGUGCCAUUGCAGUACAUUGUAAAGCUGGCCUUGGUCGCACAGGCACUCUGAUAGCCUGCUACAUCAUGAAGCAUUACAGGAUGACAGCAGCCGAGACCAUUGCGUGGGUAAGGAUCUGCAGACCUGGCUUGGUGAUCGGGCCUCAGCAGCAGUUUUUGGUGAUGAAGCAAACAAGCCUCUGGCUGGAAGGGGACUAUUUUCGUCAGAGGUUAAAGGGGCAGGAGAAUGGACAACACAGAGCAGCCUUCUCCAAACUUCUCUCUGGUGUUGAUGACAUUUCCAUAAAUGGGGUCGAGAAUCAAGACCAGCAAGAACCCAAACCUUACAGUGAUGACGACGAAAUCAAUGGAGUGACACAAGGUGAUAGAAGUCGGGCCCUGAAAAGGCGAAGACAAUCAAAAACAAACGAUAUUCUUCUCCCAUCUCCCCUGGCUGUGCUGACCUUUACACUGUGUAGUGUUGUCAUCUGGUGGAUUGUUUGUGACUACAUUCUUCCCAUCCUGCUAUUCUGACUCAAAGAUUUCAGAACAUAGUAGCCAUCAGGACCCCCUGACAGAUAGCUGCUUCUCUCCAUUUCAAGGACUAAAAUGGUUUUGCAUUAAGUAAAAACCUGUGACCAGAACUGAAGGAAGACUCUAGGAACUGAAAACUGCAACAGAAAUUAGCACAAUUUGAAAACAAAACAAAAUUGCAAAAGACUUAGUUGCUUUCCACCUAAGAAGCUAAUCAAUGGGGAAAAUGUCCACGGGGUUUCAGUAAUGAACUUUUGAGUUUGGGUGCAAGCAAAUGUACCAAGACCAGCUCAGUCAGGGAGACCCUACCCCAGUGGUGCUAGAGGAAUUAAAGACACACACACAGAAAUACAGAGGUGUAAAGUGGGAAAUCAGGGGUCUCACAGCCUUCAGAGCUGAGAGCCCCGAACAGAGAUUUACCCACAUAUUGAUUAACAGCAAACAAGUCAUUAGCAUUGUUUCUAUAGAUAUUAAAUUAACUAAAAGUAUCCCUUAUGGGAAACGAAGGGAUGGGCCUAAUUAAAGGCAUAGGUUGGGCUAGUUAACUGCGGCAGGAGCACGUCCUUAAGGCACAGAUGGCUCAUGCUAUUGUUUGUGGCUUAAGAAUGCCUUUAAGCAGUUUUCCACUCUGGGCUGGGUGGGCCAGGUGUUCCUUGCCCUCAUUCCGGUAAACCCACACCCUUCCAGCGUGGGCAUUAGGGCCAUUAUGAACAUGUUACAGUGCUGCAGAGAUUUUAUUUAUGGCCAGUUUUGGGGCCAGUUUAUGGCUGGAUUUUGGGGGGCUUGCUCCCAAAAAGAAUGACUCAAAGAAAGGCCCAGCUCUCAAGCUGAAUGACAAAAAUGCUGUUGUAAAUUUAGUCUCAGGUGUAAAUACCCAAGCCCUCUGGUACUCAGGGAGCUGGCUGGUCUGUGGUGCAUGUGUGUCCUUGUGAUGGCAAGCAUUGUAGUUGAUGGCCUUCAGAAGAAUUGAGGAUCUGAUGGAGGUUUUUUAAUGUAUUUAUUUUCUGUUCAGCUUGUGACCCUGUGUCAAAAUUUGUAAAGAUACAAAAGGCAUUACUGAAAUGGUACUUUCUGUAAUUUGAUACUAUUUGGCUUUACCAUCUUCACUUGACUGUUUGUAAUACUGUAGUAAUAUUAACUCUGAUAAGUACCCAAGCUGCUUGUCUUCUACCAAAGAGUGCUUUAUUAACAAGAAUCUGUGAAAACCACAUUUUAAACACUGUUGCAUGUUGUAAUACCAGGUGAUACCUUGGUAACCUAAAACUUGCAAGAGAAUAUUAGUGGUAGCUUUAGAAGACUCAGGAGGAGAAACUGACUUCAGAGCUGGAAGAUGUUGCAAGUCAUUCCUUUUUCUGUCCUUUAGGGACUGAAGAACUGGGAGGUUGCCCAUUGUUUGGUUGCCAGUCAUACAAAUUAAAAUCAUAUUUCCUUCCAUGCA